CAGUUAGUACACUGAAAUUCAAAGUCAUGCUCAUAACUGUUAAUGAAAGCAGAUUCAAAGCAACACCACCACCACUGAAGUAUUUUUAGUUAUAUAAGAUUGGAACUACCAAGCAUGUGGCUCCUGGUCAGUGUAAUUCUAAUCUCACGGAUAUCCUCUGUUGGGGGAGAAGCAACAUUUUGUGAUUUUCCAAAAAUAAACCAUGGAAUUCUAUAUGAUGAAGAAAAAUAUAAGCCAUUUUCCCAGGUUCCUACAGGGGAAGUUUUCUAUUACUCCUGUGAAUAUAAUUUUGUGUCUCCUUCAAAAUCAUUUUGGACUCGCAUAACAUGCACAGAAGAAGGAUGGUCACCAACACCAAAGUGUCUCAGACUGUGUUUCUUUCCUUUUGUGGAAAAUGGUCAUUCUGAAUCUUCAGGACAAACACAUCUGGAAGGUGAUACUGUGCAAAUUAUUUGCAACACAGGAUACAGACUUCAAAACAAUGAGAACAACAUUUCAUGUGUAGAACGGGGCUGGUCCACCCCUCCCAAAUGCAGGUCCACUGACACUUCCUGUGUGAAUCCGCCCACAGUACAAAAUGCUCAUAUACUGUCGAGACAGAUGAGUAAAUAUCCAUCUGGUGAGAGAGUACGUUAUGAAUGUAGGAGCCCUUAUGAAAUGUUUGGGGAUGAAGAAGUGAUGUGUUUAAAUGGAAACUGGACAGAACCACCUCAAUGCAAAGAUUCUACGGGAAAAUGUGGGCCCCCUCCACCUAUUGACAAUGGGGACAUUACUUCAUUCCCGUUGUCAGUAUAUGCUCCAGCUUCAUCAGUUGAGUACCAAUGCCAGAACUUGUAUCAACUUGAGGGUAACAAGCGAAUAACAUGUAGAAAUGGACAAUGGUCAGAACCACCAAAAUGCUUACAUCCGUGUGUAAUAUCCCGAGAAAUUAUGGAAAAUUAUAACAUAGCAUUAAGGUGGACAGCCAAACAGAAGCUUUAUUUGAGAACAGGUGAAUCAGCUGAAUUUGUGUGUAAACGGGGAUAUCGUCUUUCAUCACGUUCUCACACAUUGCGAACAACAUGUUGGGAUGGGAAACUGGAGUAUCCAACUUGUGCAAAAAGAUAGAAUCAAUCAUAAAAUGCACACCUUUAUUCAGAACUUUAGUAUUAAAUCAGUUCUUAAUUUCAUUUUUAAGUAUUGUUUUACUCCUUUUUAUUCAUACGUAAAAUUUUGGAUUAAUUUGUGAAAAUGUAAUUAUAAGCUGAGACCGGUGGCUCUCUUCUUAAAAGCACCAUAUUAAAACUUGGAAAACUAA